ACGGCCUCGCCUCGGUAUCGCAGCGGGUCCUCUCUAUCUAGCUCCAGCCUCUCGCCUGCGCCCCACUCCCCGCGUCCCGCGUCCUAGCCGACCAUGGCCGGGCCCCUGCGCGCCCCGCUGCUCCUGCUGGCCAUCCUGGCCGUGGCCCUGGCCGUGAGCCCCGCGGCCGGCUCCAGUCCCGGCAAGCCGCCGCGCCUAGUGGGAGGCCCCAUGGACGCCAGCGUGGAGGAGGAGGGUGUGCGGCGUGCACUGGACUUUGCCGUCGGCGAGUACAACAAAGCCAGCAACGACAUGUACCACAGCCGCGCGCUGCAGGUGGUGCGCGCCCGCAAGCAGAUCGUAGCUGGGGUGAACUACUUCUUGGACGUGGAGCUGGGCCGAACCACGUGUACCAAGACCCAGCCCAACUUGGACAACUGCCCCUUCCAUGACCAGCCACAUCUGAAAAGGAAAGCAUUCUGCUCUUUCCAGAUCUACGCUGUGCCUUGGCAGGGCACAAUGACCUUGUCGAAAUCCACCUGUCAGGACGCCUAGGGGACCCUGAUGAAAAGACUGAGGAAAAUGCUGCCUUUCCUGAAUGGCUACCAGGCAGGGAAUGAUGCUGGGAAGUGUUUACCCCACAGGCUCUGUGCCUUCUCUGACUGGGCAGCUCAUGCUGUAUGCAUGGAGGCAUCAUUACCAAACACACCUCUGAGGCCAGCGGCCAGCGUCUGACUCACAAGCCAUGACUGCCCCACCUUCUUACAACAACAAUAGCAGUUUCCCCGUGAGGAUUCACCCCUCCUCCCCUCUCACUCCGCCUUUUUCCAGGGAAGCUGACUCUACCCUUUGGACCACAGCUUGGAGCACUUGACCCUGGCUAAGCUGGUCAGGGCAGCGGGUCUCCCUCCCCUGAAGCCUCAUGAUUGGCAUGAGGACAACACGUGACCUAUGUGUGGCUGCCCAGGACCCACAUAGGCUUAACGGUGGGAUUUUGUUUGACUGUGUGAUAAGUGGGUUCUUCCUUCCCUGCUGAGUGUGAAGAUAAAAAAGACUUGAGGUCUGGGGCCCACUUGGAGCCUGUUUGAGAAUGAAGCCAAGUUAUGGGAAGCAACAAAACUGAAGAGACAGCAAGGAAACCAGGCCUGGUGGUGCACUCCCAGCUAUUCUGGAGGCUGACGCGGGAGGACUGCGUGAGCUCAGCAGUUUGAGGCUGCAAUGAGCCAUGAUUUCACUACUGAACUCCAGCCUGGGCAAAAGAGCGAGACCCUGUGUCUCAGAAAAAGAGAGAGAGAAACAGAGAGCAAGGAGCAGGUGGGUUAUAAUGGAGUCCCUGCACCAAGCAGAGCCUGAUGCCCGCCCUUGCUCUGAACUUCCUAGUUAUGUGAACCAACCACCAGGCCAGUUGGGUUGGGUUUCCAGCCCUGUGCUCUUGUCUGUCCUCACUGACAGACAAAAAUAACUCAUCAGUCGGUUCUCAGACCCACAGUCCCAUGACAUUUCUUGACUGUUUCAGAAGUAAUGCCUCAAGGACCAGCUUGCAGAAAGUGGAGGACCUGCCCCCUGGACCUUACAAGUAGCAGGCCACUCUUAAAAAUGCAAGGACCACAGAUGUCACCAUGACUGAAAAAUAGAGGCUGGCCCUGCCUCUGAAGAUGCUGCAAUGGACUUGUGUUCAAGGAGAAAUUGGCUGUAACUUCCCUUAUUGAGAUAUAAUCGGGCUCAUCGUUAAGCUGUGGUCAGCCAGAAGUGUAGCUGUGCCCCUGGGAUUGAAAUCAGCAAUCAAUCUGGACAUCCUUUUUCUAUCUUCAUGAGGCACCUCCCCAGUACCAACCAAAUUUCUUGGGGAUCCCCCGGGACUUCUCAUAAAUGGAAUUGAUUUGAACUCAGGAAACCCUCAAAUAGGCCAGAACAACUCACUAAUUAAAUUCAUCCCCUCCCAAAAACAAAAACAAAAACAAAAAAAAACAACACACAUGAUAGGAAAAAAAUUUUGCAAAUUAUAUAUCUGAUAUAGAACUUGUAUUCAGAACAUAUAAUGAACUCUUACAACUCAAUAAGACUGGUAACCCAAUUAAAAAUUCUUUUUAAAAAAACCAAUUUAAAAAUAAAGGCAAAUAACCUAAUUUUUAUAUAACUCAAAGUUUUUAAAGAAACAAACCAAUUUAAAAGUUCCAAAGGAUUUGAAUAAACGUUUUUCCAAAGAAGAUAUGUAAAUAGCCAAUAAACGCAUAAAAACGUGCAUAACACCAUUAGCUAUUAGGAAAAGGCAAAUCAAAACCACAGUAAAAAGCAGCUUCAAAGCCACUACAUGGUUGUGGUCAAAGAGACCACAAAUAACAAAUUGGAAUCUUUAUACAUAGCUGGUGGGAAUGUAAAAUGGUGCAGCUGCUUUGGAAAACAGUUUCACAAGUUUUCAAAAGGUUAGACCUACCAUAUAACCUAGCAACUCUACUCAUAUUUAUAUGUCAGCUACAAAUAAAAACAUUAAGUUCACCAAAAUAUUUACACAUGAAAGUUCAUAGCAUCAUUAUUAAAAUCAGAAAAAAAUAUAUUAAAAAAAACCUCAAAUGUCCAUCAACUGACGAAUGGAUAAUCAAGAUAUAGUGUUAGUCUAUUCAUACAAUGGAAAAUGAACGGGCAUAAAAGAGAAUGACAUGACCCGUGCUACAAUGUGGAGCAAUCUUGAAAAUGUGCUAAGUGAAAGAAGCCAGCAAGCCAUGCUGAAACAAGUCAGCAUUCAUACAAUAUGAUUCAAUUUAUAUGAAAUACCCAGAACAGAAAAAUGUAUAGAGACAGGCUGUAGAUUAGUGGUUGUCUAGGGCUGGGGGCAAUAGAAGGCAGAGUGACUGCUAAUAGGAAGUUUCCUUGGAGGGAUCAUGAAAAUGUUCUAAAAUCAGAUUAUACGUCCAUUUGCACAAUUUUGUGAAUAUACUCGGAACCACUGAAUUGUAUACUUUAAGUGGGUGAGGUAUGUGAAAAUUAAAUGUCAGUAAAGCUGUUUAAAAAAGUUUCAUCCCAAAGCUACAUUUUACCUAAGGCAAAUGUUUACUACCGCUUCUCUUUCAGUCCCAAAUAAUUUCCAGCCAUAUGUUCCAGUCAAGCCUCGACAAAAUUAAACAACACCACAACUUACUCCAGUUACAAGCCAAUGUGCAAAUGCCCCAAACUUGACCAUAAAUUUACCACCCAACCCCCAUCGUCUCAUUCCCAGGAAAAACUAAACACAAGAUCAACUCCCCUUGCAAGUUGAAGUCCUGACAUUGAAGUCUAAAGAAAUCACAGCCCACAAUAAAAUUCUUAAAGUGUACAAACAA